AGUGCUGAGGGGGCGCGGCGCGGAGGGGCGCGGAGCGGCGCGGAGCCGGGCGGCUCGGGGCCCAGAGAGAGCCGCGGCCGGGAGCUCGCGGGCUCCUGACAACCUCCUCCCCUCGGCGGACGACGACCACGGCGACUAGGGCGCCGGUCAUGGCGGAGCAACAAACCCGGCGCGGACCCUAGGCACCACCGCAUGGAGCGGGACGAACCGCCGCCUAGCGGAGGGGGAGGCGGCGGGGGCUCGGCGGGGUUCCUGGAGCCUCCCGCCGCGCUCCCUCCGCCGCCGCGCAACGGUUUCUGUCAGGAUGAAUUGGCAGAGCUUGACCCAGGCACUAUUUCUGUUUCAGAUGAUCGGGCUGAACAACGAACCUGUCUCAUUUGUGGGGACCGCGCUACAGGCUUGCACUAUGGGAUCAUCUCCUGUGAGGGCUGCAAAGGGUUUUUCAAGCGGAGCAUUUGCAACAAACGGGUAUAUCGAUGCAGUCGUGACAAGAACUGUGUCAUGUCUCGGAAGCAGAGGAACAGGUGCCAGUACUGCCGCCUGCUCAAAUGCCUCCAGAUGGGGAUGAACCGGAAGGCUAUCAGAGAAGAUGGCAUGCCUGGAGGCCGGAAUAAGAGCAUUGGGCCAGUCCAGAUAUCGGAAGAAGAAAUCGAAAGGAUCAUGUCUGGGCAGGAGUUUGAGGAAGAGGCCAAUCACUGGAGCAACCAUGGUGAUAGUGACCACAGUUCCCCUGGGAACAGGGCUUCGGAGAGCAACCAGCCCUCACCAGGCUCCACACUGUCUUCCAGUAGGUCUGUGGAACUGAAUGGAUUCAUGGCCUUCAGGGAACAGUACAUGGGAAUGUCUGUGCCUCCACAUUACCAAUAUAUACCGCACCUUUUUAGCUAUUCUGGCCACUCACCACUUCUGCCCCAACAAGCUCGCAGCCUGGAUCCCCAGUCAUACAGUCUGAUUCACCAGCUGUUAUCAGCCGAGGACCUGGAACCAUUGGGCACGCCCAUGUUGAUUGAAGAUGGAUACGCUGUGACACAGGCAGAACUAUUUGCCCUGCUUUGCCGCCUGGCCGACGAGCUGCUCUUUAGGCAGAUUGCCUGGAUCAAGAAACUGCCUUUCUUCUGCGAGCUCUCAAUCAAGGAUUACACGUGCCUCUUGAGCUCUACGUGGCAGGAGCUAAUCCUGCUGUCUUCCCUCACCGUUUACAGCAAGCAGAUCUUUGGGGAACUGGCUGAUGUCACUGCCAAGUACUCGCCCUCCGAUGAAGAACUACACAGAUUUAGUGAUGAAGGGAUGGAGGUGAUCGAGCGGCUCAUCUACCUCUAUCACAAGUUCCAUCAGCUAAAGGUCAGCAACGAGGAGUAUGCUUGCAUGAAAGCAAUUAACUUCCUAAAUCAAGAUAUCAGGGGUCUGACCAGUGCCUCACAGCUGGAACAAUUGAAUAAACGAUACUGGUACAUUUGCCAGGAUUUUACUGAAUAUAAAUACACACAUCAGCCGAACCGCUUUCCUGAUCUCAUGAUGUGCUUACCUGAGAUUCGAUAUAUUGCAGGAAAGAUGGUGAAUGUGCCCCUGGAGCAGCUGCCCCUCCUCUUUAAGGUGGUGCUGCAUUCCUGCAAGACCAGUGUGGGCAAGGAAUGACCUGUUCCAGGCGCCCUCCUCAGGCCAACCACAGCGUCUUGGGUGGGCAGGACAGGCUCUGGAGGGAAAAGCCAGAGAGACCAAGAUGGAGGCUGUGGAGCAGCAUUUCCCGUUGCCUCCAUAGCAAGAAGAGUUUUUGUUUGUUUGUCUGUUUUUUUAACCUCAUUUUUCUAUAUAUUUAUUUCACGACAGAGUUGAAUGUAUGGCCUUCAACAUGAUGCACAUGCUUUUGUGUGAAUGCAGCCAAUGCAUUUUCUUACAGUUUACAGAAUGUGAAGAUGUUUAAUGUUACAGUGUUGUCAUUGUUUAGAAAUAGUUCUUUUGUAUUUUGAGGGAGAGGGUGGGAUGGGGCUAAGAUGACUAUUUCCAUAAUGUUGACAAAGAUGACUACCUCAAUGGAAAUGGGGGGUGUGGCCAUCCCUACUUUUUCCACAUUUUCUCAGCAGACUCAUACAUUUGUCUGUCAGAGAGCAAAUUGCCUUUUUUAGCCACAGAAUUGCCAGAUAAAACGGCACACUGUAAGGGGGCAAAGUGUUGUUAGGAGAUUCACUAAGCAAGGUUGGUGAGACGGCAACAGGGUAGGAGGUGAGGAUUGAGCCACGUCCUUUCCUUGGAAAGCGUGAAAAUUAAGAGAGUAGGGCACAGUGACCAUAUUUAAGGCAGGUGUCCUUCCACCCAACAAGUCCUAAGGGCAGAAGAAUUUCUGUUCUCACACCUUGCUGCCCCCCUUACCCCUGCACCACCAUCAUUGUCUACCACUGCGAACUUUCCAUCUAGGCAAAGUCCUGGCAAUCACUUGAUCCACAGGACUCGCCUCCCAGCUCCCUCGGGGCCCCCAGCUACCUAGUUUCCUUACCUGGAUCUCCUGAGGCCCACCUUCCUCCUUCCCACUCCCUUACACAUUUGACUUCCUAUUGGCCCUUUGAAAAACCAGCUGAGCAGAAUGCCAUGUUCUGAAGCCUGGUGCCCACUACUGAUUUAUUCUCCUUUCACCUUGUUUUCUUCAAAGGGUAGUAGGGCAAGGCCAGACUGCAAAAAGAAUAGACACUCCCCUUUUGAAAUCUGUUCCUCUCCCCUCCCCUUCCUACCGCACCCUCAGGUCUAAAUCCGAAAACUUCAGGCUUUUUUAAACAAUGAGAAGGACCAUUCACCUGUCUGCUGACCAGAAAUGUUGCCCCUAAGUUCUUCUCCAAGUUCUCCUUUUCUCUCCAGAGUGAGACCAGUUUUCCUCAGGGACCCAGGACACAAAGCCCAAGGCCCAGAGUGGCUCAGCUGCCCCUUACUUCAGCAGUGGACUGGCCAGCCAAGGCCUGGAGGGCUGGAGCCAGAAGCACCUGGAAGGGAAGGGGGGCUUUAAACUACCUCAGGUUCCUAAUGGCCCGGCUGCUACCUCUGCAGACAUGGCCUGGACUCCUUGACCUCUCACUACCUGCCCCACCUUAUCCCAGGACGUGUUCCUUACCCUCUUGACUUUGGCCAGCGCUACACCAGGUCUGUCUUUGAACUCUUUCAGGUGCUUGUCCUGCCUACACCCAGGUAUCUUUCACAGCCAGUGUGGCAAGCAGACCACUUAGUUGGCUGCAUGCCUGGGUAGGUUGGAAGGGCCCACGGCACCUUCUUCUGCCUAUUUAGUCAAAGGCUGUUUGCUGUCUCCUCAACUCAACCUAGUAAAGCUACCCAGGAGGGCACCACGUCGUGUGCAUACUGGGUAGUCCAUGUCUGAUUGUAAUUGUUUCUUUCUGGUGAAAUGUUACGGGUACCAGCAGAGUGAUGAUUUUGGCCCUUGAUGGAUCUAAAACUCGGAACAUUACUCCUCAAUGCCGUUUCCCCAGUUGCUCUGAGAAGGAAGAGACAUGUUCCUCAGGAAAAGCUCCAGCUAGCAUGUUUUUCACGUCAGUGGGAAGAUUCUUGUGUGUUCGUGUGUAUCUGUUUAUUUCUAAGUUCACGAUACUUGUUCCCCUGAAUUUUAUUUAACCAACUAGAUCACAUUCUUUGGCCACAGGUCAGACUCUGAGCUGCUUUCCUCCAGAUCGGGAAGGAGACACAUAUCACAGAUGCCUUCUCUAAGACAGCUCCUGUGUACAGCAUCGUUCUUUGCUGAGGCCUCUAUCUGUCCAAUUAUUAUUUUUGAAAUUGCUUUUCAAAUUAAACAUUUUACCCGUUGUGUUGGGUGUCAAAAGAAAUUGCUCUCUGAUGAGGCAAGAACAUGUCUCUCCAACAACGUAGUAUUGAACAGAGCAAGUUGUUAAUUUGUGGAGUAGGGGAAAGGUUCUGCAAGUUGCCAUUGUACAAAUCCAGUUUUACAAAUGUUUGCAGCAGAUUCCACAGAACAAAGAGCCCAUUCAUUGCCGAGAGCCCUGCAGAAUCUCAGAGCAAAGUGGCUGUGUGUUCCGAGCCGGAGCCUGACCUGUGGACCGUCUUUAAUGUCUUCUGCACCAGUCCUUUUAUGACGUGGGCUUUUUUUAAACAGGGUAAAGUGAAUGUGUUGCAUUGCAAACUCAGGUAUUAUGAGGAGAAGGUAGGAGUGUAGCUAGCAGCGUGGAGACAUUAGGUCAGCCACUAGAUGUAUUUGUGAAUUUGGUUUGAAGGACACGGAGAAAGGUUGGAGGGGAGGUUUGGUGUGUUUGUUUUUUGCUUUCUUCCCCAUAAUGUUUGGUUAACAGGUAGCCUUUUUGCGAGUGGAAGGAGAGAAAAGUUGUGCAUGUUUUCUCUAAUUUCUCUUUCUGCCCUCUCUCUGAUCCCCAACCACCAAAAGCACUCACUUUGAGUGAGGAUUUUUUUUUUUUUUUUUUUUUUUUUUUUUGAGGCGGAGUCUCGCUCUGUCGCUCAGGCUGGAGUGCAGUGGUGCGAUCUUGGCUCACUGCAAGCUCCGCCUCCCGGGUUCAUGCCAUUCUCCUGCCUCAGCCUCCUGAGUAGCUGGGACUACAGGCGCCCGCCACCACACCCGGCUAACUUUUUUUGUAUUUUUAGUAGAAACAUUGUUUCACCACGUUAGCCAGGAUGGUCUCCAUCUCCUGACCUCGUGAUCCGCCUGCCUCGGCCUCCCAAAGUGCUGGGAUUACAGGCGUGAGCCACUGCACCCAGCCGAGUGAGAAUUUUUAUGCCAUAAAAAUACGACUCUGAAAGCUACAUGGAAAAGGAGAAUCCCACCUCCUUGCACUACAUUGAAACAUGCAAGCCUUUCCCUCCCUCUCCUUUUUGAUGUUUUCUUGUCCCAAGACAAAAGUUUGGCAUCUUGGAACUUAUUCAUGCUCUCUGGCUGCCUUUGUAGACUUUUGGAGUCCUUUGCAAGGUUUGGUGGUCUCGUCGUUAAUCUGGAGAAAUUCCCCAGAAUCUGUCUCAAAGCGCUCAACCUGGCUCAGAGGACACCCAGCCCCUAUGCCCCACUCACAAGAGAGGUGGGCAAGCCCCCAGGGAUAGGAGGAAGUAAGCAGGAUCCUCCCUGUCCUGUUUCCCAGAACCAGAGCAAGGAAUGGGGAAUCCUAAGGGUUUCUGUGGCAUCACUGAAUGUCACCCACUCCACAUCAACCUGCCUCUCACCUGCCACCCUUUUUCAGGGAGGUGAGUACCUGCCAUGGUCACUGUUACCAGAUCCUUAAAAUCCUGGGCUCUGAGCUAGGUGCAUUGCUCUGUUACCCAUUUCCUACAUUUGUUUGUUUGUUCUUGAUUUCCUGGGGGAAUGGGACUGAUGGAGACAGACAAACCCACUGUGGGCAGCAUCUAAGCCAUGUCCAAGGUUGGUCGAAUUAAGGGAACCCUGGCCUCUCAGCAGGACAGAAAGCUGAGCUGUGGUUCCAGGCCCUCCUCUCUGGGCCCCUGGUGUGUAUCUUUUUUCCUUGUUGCUUUUGAAAUUUUUGCAAUUAUUUUAAGAAUCCAGUCUUUCAGACCAGCCCUUUUAUUAAGCUUUGAAUUUUUAAUUGAUUUUUUUAAAGUAAAAAAAAAAAAAACCCAAAAAACAAACAAAAUUUAACAAAAAAAUCCGCUACUCUUACUCCCCUGCCUCCCCCUACCCCAGCCCAUGAGAGUUCCCUUGCACUCCCCUCUGCCUUUGCAACUGAUCAUCCUCCCUUUCUCCUUGGCUUGAAGCAUCUAUGUCCAGUAUCUGUGAAAUGAUGUUUUAUCUGUGUGUCAGGAUGAGAAACGGCAGUCAUUCCACCAAGUGUUGGAAACUGGUUAGCCUGGAGACAAGGGUUUCUGGGGCCACAGCUCAGGGAUGUGUAUUUAAUUACAGGAUCCCCAGAAACUCCUCUCUAGGCUGCCACAGCAACAUUUUUUCUGGGCUUGGGAGCCAUACCUGAACUGUUUCCUCCAAGGCGGGAACUCCAGAGAGCCUGCCAAGUCUGGAGCAAGCUGGGGCUUCUGCUUUGGCCAGACCUGGGCCACCAUGAGACUUGAAGGCUUCUAGCUGUCCUACGACACGAGCCACGGUGGCCCUGCCUCUCCCCGCUCAUAGAAGCCUGGUCCCUCUGUCUAGCCCAGUUCCCAUCUAGCAUCCGUCUUCUGGGCCUGAAGCCCUAAAUGGACCACAGCCUGCACAGGAAUCAACUGUAGGCUCAAAGGGAGGCGGUGAGUAAGGUCAGAGCCUGCUCCAAGCCCAAGAACAAAAGUUGUGUUAUGGGUGGAGGCUAGUCCCCCAGAUCUAGCCCUGCCGUCUUUGCCCUUUAAUGACCAUUGUUUUCUUUCUCUAAAAUGUCUUGUAAUAGGUGAUAAUGUUGUUGAUUCAAAUUUCCAUGAAAAAGAAAAAAAAAACUACCUCUUAAGCGACAUCCUGGUCGAUUCCUCUCUGAGGAAUCCUGUGGGAAAAGAAUACUGUAGCUCCUGCUCUGUUUACAUGUUUCUGUCGGGAAAGAAGCCCCGCCUGCCCUGGGGUGUUGGUGUUUUUGUCUGUGUUGCCAUCCCAGGUCUGCCAUAGGGGCUGGUGGCUGCAUUGUGAUGUCUGGGCUGUGUCUGGGGAUUCCUUCCCACCUACCCAGCCAGGGACUAGUCACCCCCCUGAAGAGGCCUCCAUUUCCUUCCUGUGCUCCAGGGCAUAGGGAGCACCACUCCCACAGACACCACCUUUAAGGGCUCUAGUGGCACACACAUCCACGAGCCUACCCCCAGGUUACCUGCCCUAGGUCCACCUCCACCCACAGUCCUGUGUGUAGGAAUCGAGGAAACGGGAUGUCCCUGAGCCCUUGUCUCCAAAGGGCCGGCCAAGGGCUGCCCGCCAGCCUGACUCCAUCAACCCUCCAUGACCAAAUGAUAGCUGGCGGGCUCUGCAGGCUACCCAGGCCCUCUGCUACCUCCCACCCUGCCAGCUGGCAAGGGAUGGGCCCUGUUCUGUGAAUUGACUACCUGUGGAAAUGUGACCAAUUAGUGUGAAAUGCAUGUUUAGCAAGUGUUAGGUACUGUAUUUGAACCAAUAAAUGUGAAUCCUUCUGCACAUGG